CUCGCGCUGUUUCCGCCUCUUGCCUUCGGACGCCGGAUUUUGACGUGCUCUCGCGAGAUUUGGGUCUCUUCCUAAGCCGGCGCUCGGCAAGUUCUCCCAGGAGAAAGCCAUGUUCAGUUCGAGCGCCAAGAUCGUGAAGCCCAAUGGCGAGAAGCCGGACGAGUUCGAGUCCGGCAUCUCCCAGGCUCUUCUGGAGCUGGAGAUGAACUCGGACCUCAAGGCUCAGCUCAGGGAGCUGAAUAUUACGGCAGCUAAGGAAAUUGAAGUUGGUGGUGGUCGGAAAGCUAUCAUAAUCUUUGUUCCCGUUCCUCAACUGAAAUCUUUCCAGAAAAUCCAAGUCCGGCUAGUACGCGAAUUGGAGAAAAAGUUCAGUGGGAAGCAUGUCGUCUUUAUCGCUCAGAGGAGAAUUCUGCCUAAGCCAACUCGAAAAAGCCGUACAAAAAAUAAGCAAAAGCGUCCCAGGAGCCGUACUCUGACAGCUGUGCACGAUGCCAUCCUUGAGGACUUGGUCUUCCCAAGCGAAAUUGUGGGCAAGAGAAUCCGCGUCAAACUAGAUGGCAGCCGGCUCAUAAAGGUUCAUUUGGACAAAGCACAGCAGAACAAUGUGGAACACAAGGUUGAAACUUUUUCUGGUGUCUAUAAGAAGCUCACGGGCAAGGAUGUUAAUUUUGAAUUCCCAGAGUUUCAAUUGUAAACAAAAAUGACUAAAUAAAAAGUAUAUAUUCACAGUAC